UUCUGCUGAGAGAUCUGCUGUUAGUCUGAUGGGCUUCCCUUUGUGAGUAACCUGACCUUUCUCUCUGGCUGCCCUUAACAUUGUUUUCCUUCAAUUCAAUCUUGGUAAAUCUGACAAUUAUGUGUCUUGGGGUUGCUCUUCUCAAGGAAUAUCUUUAUGGUGUUCUCUGUAUUUCCUGAAUUUGAAUGUUGGCCUGCCUUGCUAGGUUGGGGAAAUUCUCCUGGAUAAUAUCCUGAAGAGUGUUUUCCAACUUGGUUCCAUUCUCCCUGUCACUUUCAGUUUCACCAAUCAAACGUAGAUUUGGUCUUUUCACCUAGUCCCAUAUUUCUUGGAGGCUUUGUUCAUUUCUGUUUACUCUUUUUUCUCUAAACUUCUCCUCUUGCUUUAUUUCAUUCAUUUGAUCUUCAGUCACUGAUACCCUUUCUUCCACUUGAUCAAAUCGGCUACUGAAGCUUGUACAUGCAUCAUGUAGUUCUUGCGCCAUGGUUUUCAGCUCCAUCAGGUCAUUUAAGUUCUUUUCUACACUGUUUAUUCUAGUUAGCUAUUCGUCUAAUCUUUUUUCAAGGUUUUUAGCUUCCUUGCGAUAGGUUCAAACAUCCUCAUUUAGCUUGGAGAAGUUUCUUAUUCCUGACCUUCUGAAGCCUACUUCUGUCAACUUGUCAAAAUCAUUGUCUGUCCAGCUUUGUUCUGUUACUGGCGAGGAGCUGCAAUCCUUUGGAGGAGAAGAGGUGCUCUGGUUUUUAGAAUUUUCAGCUUUUCUAUUCUGGUUUCUCCCCAUCUUUGUGGUUUUUAUCUACCUUUGGUCUUUGAUGUUGGUGACCUACAGAUGGGGUUUUGGUGUGGAUAUCCUUUUUGUUGAUGUUGAUCCUAUUCCUUUCCGUUUGUUGGUUUUCCUUUUAACAGUCAGAUCCCUUAGCUGCAGGUGUGUUGGAGUUUGCUGGAGGUCUACUCCAGACCGUGUUUCCCUGGGGAUCACCAGCAGAGGCUGCAGAACAACAAAGAUUGCAGAACAGCAAAUAUUUCUGCCUGAUCCUUCUGGAAGCUUUGUUCCAGAGGGGCACCUGCCUGUAUGAGGUGUCAAUCAGCCCCCUACUGGAAGGUGUCUCCAGUUAGGCUACACAGGGGUCAGGGACCCACUUGAGGAGGUAGUCUGUCCGUUCUCAGAGCUCAAACACCAUGCUGGGAGAACCACUGCUCUCUUCACAGCUGUGAGACGGGGACGUUUAAGUCUGCAGAAGUUUCUGCUGCCUUUUCUUCAGUUAUGCCCUGCCCCCAGACGUGGAGUCUACAGAGGCAGCAGGCCUUGGUGAGCUGUGGUGCGCUCUGCCCAGUUCAAGCUUCCCUGACUGCUUUGUUUACCUACUCAAGCCUCAGCAAUGGUGGACGCCCCUCCCCCUGCCAGGUUGCUGCCUCACAGAUCCUUCUCAGACUGCUGUGCUGGCAGUGAGCAAGGCUCCAUAGGCGUAGGACCUAUCCAGCCAUGCAGGGGAUAUAAUCUCCUGGUGUGCCGUUUGCUAAGACCAUUGGAAAAGUACAGUAUUUAGGCAGGAGUGUCCUGUUUUUCCAGGUAUGGUCUGUCACAGUUUCCCUUGGCUAGGAAAGGGAAAUCCCUCGACCCCUGCACUUCCUGGGUGAGGCAACGCCUCGCCCUGCUUCGGCUCGCCCUCCAUGGGCUGCACCCACUGUCCAACCCAUCCCAAUGAGAUGAACCAGGUACCUCAGUUGGAAAUGCAGAAAUCACCCAUCUUCUGCGUUGAUCACAGUGGGAGCUGUAGACCAGAGCUGUUCCUAUUCGGCCAUCUUGGAAUGGGAUCCUGUGUUGUUUUUUUUUAAUUGUUUACUUUUUGUCCCUCAAACUAGCUAAUCUCAAUCAAUCUUCAGGUUUACUAUUUCUUCUGCCUGCUCAAAACUGCAGUUGAGCCGCUGUAGUGAAGUUUUCAUUUUAGUUAUUAUGCUUUUUAACUCCAGAAUUGCUAUUUAAUUUAAAAAAAUAAUUUAUGUAUCACUAAGGUUUGAAUGUGUCUCCCAAAAGUUUAUGUGCUGGAAAGUUAAUUGUCAUUGUAACAGUAUUAAGAGUUAGGACCUUUAAGAGGUGAUUAGGUCAUAAGAGCUCUGCCCUCAUGAAUAUAUUAAUGCUAUUAUCAUGGUUUAGUUAUUACAGCCUUGGGGCUCCUGAUAAAAUGAUGAGUUUGGCCUGGUUUCCUCACUCUCUCUUGCAUGCUUGCUUACCAUGUGAUGCCUUCCACCAUGAGAUGAUAUUCACCAGGUGCUAGUGCCAUGCUCUUCGACUUCCUAGUCUCUAGAACCAUGAGCCAAAUAAGCUUCUGUUCUUUAGAAAUUAUUCAGCCUGUGGUAUUCUGUUAUAGCAGCAGAAAAUGGACUAAAACAUAUAUAUUUAUUGAUCAUCUAUAUUUGGUGUAAUAUAAUAUAUUUAUACCUUUAUACUUUCUUUUAGUUCUUUUCUUUUCUUUCUUUUUUUUUUUCUUUUUUUUUUUUUUGGAGAUAGCUUCUUGCUUUGUCACCCAAGCUGGAGUGUAGUAGUGUGAUCAUAGCUCACUGAAGCCUCAAACUCCUGAGCUCAAGUAAUCCUCCCACCUUAGUCUCCCAAGUAGCUCAGACCAUAUGUGCAUGCCACCAUGCCUGGCUGAUUCUUUACAUUACUAGAGAUAGGGUCUAGCUCUGUUGCCAAGGCUGGUCUUGAACUCCUGGGAUCAAGCAGUUCUUCCCCCUCAGCUUCCCAAAGUGCUGGGUUUAUAGGCGUGAGCCACCAUGCCCAGCCUCUUUUAGUUCUUUAGACAUGGUUUCUUUCAGCACUUUGAACAUAUUUAAAACGGUUCAUUUAAAGUCUUUGUCUAGUAAGUUCAACAUUUGGGCCUCCUUAGGGCAGUUUCCACUGAUUACUUUGUUUUCCUUCUGUAUGGGCCAUGUUUGCUUGUUUUCUUUCCCAUAUCUCAUAAUUUUUUGUUGAAAAUUGGACAUUUUAUAUGUGGCAACUCUGGAAAUAAGAUACUCUCCCCUCCCCAGGGUGUUUUGUUGCUGCUGGUUGUAGUGGUAGUAGUUUGGUGACCUUUCUGAACUACUUGUCUGAAGACUAUAAUCUAUAUUGUUUGUGACCAUUGAAGUGUCUACUUGUUUAUCUUGGUGGUCAGCUAAUGAUUGGAAAAGAUUUCCUCCAAUGCCUAGAAGCAAUAAAUCACCCAUUCUUUGCCAAGGAACUCUACGUGCAUGUUGGGCUACACUUGCAACACUAAGCAAGGUGGUUGACAACUUACCUUAGCCUUCACUUCCUGCUUGUGCAGAGCUUCCAGGUCAGCCAGAGAUUAGAGUUUAGGAGCUUCUCAAGUCUUUCCUGUGCAUGCAUAUAGCCCUAUGUGUGUGUGUAGCUUCCUAGAUUCCUAGGAAUAUGUUGGAGUUUUUCAAAGCCCCUACAGAGAUCUAAUUUUCCAGCUUUUUCUUUUAAACUUUUUGGUUAGUCUGUUGUUGCUCCAAGUGUUAUCAACUGCCUUGGGCAACUGUGAAGUUAAAACACCUGCUUGUAAUUAUUUUCAACAAUUACAAAUCCCUGGGAAGGAGGCAUUUUGUACUGGCAAGCCCUGAGUUAGGCCAAAUACAGACUGACUUAUAAGUGGGUUAUUCCAGGGAACCACUAGAUGGUAAAAUAAUGACAGUUCUUGGGAAUGAACAUUUGAAAGAGCCCUAGCUCCAUUUUCCUUUCUCCAGUAGCUGUUAAGCUGCACCAGGAUUGUGGGUUAUUACUUUUCACGAUUAUUUUUAUUGUGGAGAUAAGGGAGUCAGAGAUGGGACUAAGGCAAGUUAAAAUGCCACGAAGCUUGUUGUUCUUACUGAUAUUCAUUCAUUCACACAUGCAUGCUUUUUGGGUUACUGCAAGCCUUUAGUUAAUAUCUAGAGUUAUGAAAAAGUUUAUUCUGAUUUUUUUUGCCAUUUUUUCAUUGCUUUUGUGGAUGAGAAAAAUUUUGGAGAUCCUUAAUCUGCCAUUUUUGCUGAUGGUAUUCCACAGCUCAACUUUUAAAUAUAAUUUUUUAGUCUUCAUCUUAUUUGAAAAUUUUGAGCCAUUUGGCUUUUGACCAAUCUUCCCUUCAAGAAAUGACCUCCUUGCUGCCUUUAUGGACACCGUUUCCAUUCUUCAGUCCACUGAAGACUUCCUCUGAUUAUCCUUUAGAAGUUAAUGUUAUUCAGAAUUCUUUUCUUGGUUCUCUUGUUUCCAUUCUACAUAUCCUUCCUGGAUGAUCUCACCUAUAUGCAUGACUUCAGGUGCCUUUUCUAUGAAGUAACUCUCUUUCUCUCUCUCUCUCUUUUUUUUUUUUUUUUUUUUUGAGACUGGGUCUCACUGUGUCACUCAGGCUGGAGUCCAGUGGCAUGAUCACAACUCACUGCAGGCUUGACCUCCUGGGCUCAGGUGAUCCUCCUAUGUCAGCCUCCUGAGUAGCUGGGACUACAGGUGUGUCACCACGCCUAGCUAAUUUUUGUACUUUUUGUAGAGACGGGGUCUUGCCAUAGUGCCCUGACUGGUCUCAAACUCUUGGGCGCAAGCAGUCCACCAGCCUCUGCCUCCCAAAGUGCUAGGAUUACAGUCAUGAGCCACUGUGCCCGGCCUCUGUGAAAUAACUCUUAAAUUCAUGUUUUCUACCUAGAUUUCUCCUUGUCUCUGGUCCUAAAUAUCCACUACCUCUUACAACUCCAUUUUGGUGUAAUUAAGACAAAGCAAACUUGGCACAUCCCAAACUGAACUGGUUAUUUUACUCCAGAUCUGUUCUUCCUCCUGUCUUUACUGUCUCAGUAAAUGGCUGCUAUCUAUCUCAGUUUUCAAUGUAUUGACUUUUCUCUUUCCCUCAUCAGGUCAUAACUGAUUAGUUACCAAGUUCUAUCACUAUACAUCUUAAAUACCUCUAGAAUUUGUCUACUUUUCCCAUCCCUGAUUCUGCUUUCCUAGUUAAGGCCACAAUUUCAUCUUGCUUAAAACAAUUGUAAUGAUUUGCUGCUUUACAUCUCCUGCCUUGUCCUGCCUUCUAUACAUUCUCUAUACUGAAGGUAGAAUGUGCUUUCCAAAAAGCACAUCUUAUUAUGUCAUUCUCUCACCUGAUAAACAGUGACUAACAACAUAAACACCAUCUCUGCCUUCAGGGAGCUUUGGGUAUAGUGAAGGAUACAGACAAGGAGGUGACCAAGUACAAUUCAGAGUAUGAUAUAGUAAGUGUACAUAGGAGAGGCAGAGACUCAACCAAGACUCAAGAUUUUAAGAGAAUUUCAGGGGAGAUGAUGUCUAAGCUAAGAUUUGCAGGAAGAGUAGGAAUUAUACAGAUGAAGAGAGGAAUGGGAAAGAGUGUUCCAGGCUGAGAGUACACAUAAGAAGGCCUAGAGAAAGCACUGGAUUCCAGGAAAUGAAAGAAGUUCUGUAUGUUGGCAAAUUUUGUUAAGGAAGUAGUAUGAGUUAAGCCUGAAGAAGUAAGCUGAGACCAUAUCACACAGGCUCCUGUAUGUCAUGUUAAGGGAUCACUUUAAUCUCAGUGCUUUUGGGAGCCACUGAAGUGGUUUUUGUUGGGAAGAAAUAUGAUCAGAUUUGCAUAUUAGAAAGAGUAUUCUGGCUAGAGUAUGGAGAAAGCUUUGAGAGUAUGGAGAUCAGAUGGCUUAGUUGGAGUCAGGUUGACCAGUUAGGAAACUCUUGCAGUAAUCCAGGCAAGAGAUGAUAGUGGUGUGGACUAGGAUUGUGAUAUUUGGAAUAGAGAAAACUGAUGGAUUUGAGAAGUGUUUUAGAAAUAGAAUGGACUUGUCAAUGUUGAAUGUGGAGACUGAGGGAGAGGGAGAAGCUAAACAAAAUUGUUUGCAUUAUUUAGUUAAUAAAGCUAUCUAUUUCAAUAGCUAUUUAGAACAUAAAGCUAUUAUAUGUUUUCAAGUAUGUACAUAUAUUACUGACGAGAAAGUAGUGUUUUGUAGUUUUCUUUGAAAAAUUAUGCCUGAUGUAAGUCUAAUGACUUAAGCUCCACUAAGUAGAGUUUACUGUUCAUUUGGCAAAAGCUAUACAGCCAAUGACUGAGUCAACUUAUUUAUUUCUGUGAGCCUAGCCUUGUAUUUCCUAUUGAGAUUCAGUGAUUAAACUGGUCAACUUUAUAGUCAACUUUUUCUUUUCUGUUAUAAGCAUAAAGCUACAUGAAAUUGUUGCUGUUAGUUUUCCAAGGCUACACAAAGAUGUUUCUACUCUGGACUUUUCACAAUAAAGCAACCAAUAGAACAUUUUUGCAAUUUUCUGUUUGUAGUAUAGUGGAAUAUCUGACUAAAGUCCUGCUGAUUUUAGGUUCAGUUUGACUUGGUCACUUUUUAAUAAGACAAAUUUAUGUCUACAUGACUUUUGUUAUCUGGUUAAAAAGUGUGCUUUGAAACAACGUUCUUUGAAUUUGAAGGCCUGUGUAAAAGUAUAUAAUUUUAUCACUAAUACAUGAAAAGAGAAUCACUUACAAUUUUUGCAGAAGAGGUCUGGAAACUCAUAUUUUUAGACUUUAUAUUCUUCUGCAUGGACUUUUUGGAAAUUAUAAACUUAUAACCUCUACUUCCCAAAUUAUUCUGGUAUUUGUUAAAUGGCUAUGUGGUUGGAUACAGUAUUGUUCAACAAAAGUAGCUUUCAGUUUAAUUUUAAUCAGAAUCAUCAAUGUAUUUUUAUUUUAGGAAAUAAAGGAAAACAAUAUUAUUUUUUCAAAUGUUACAGAAGACAUUUUUAAUCUUCAUUUUUAAAGGGACAUGAUGAUUUCCUUUUAGAAGAGAAAAAUCCCUUGGCUCCAAAAGAGAAAUCCUCUCUCUUCUCAGUUGCCUUUAAAAUCUUGAACCUGUCAGUGAAAUUGUAUAAUCUACUAAUAACAUGCCUAAGGCUUAUUGCCUUUUCUUGGGCAACAGAAUCACCAAUUGAUGUGCUCUAUCGAUUUUAAUCACACUGUUUUUAUAGUUCCAUUGCAAGGUUUCAAAAACUCACCAAAUAAAUCUGUGGAUACAGAUGCCUCCUUUCUCUGAAAACCUAAUCAUAUAUAUACUAUUCCUUCUCAAUCAGUUGUUAAGGUAUAAUAUAGUCAAAUAAUUUUUAUUUGAUAGACUUUGGUCUUGGCUAAAUUAAAAUGUUCUCUUUGCUAUUCAGCAUUUACAUAUUUAAAUUAUACAAUUCUUAUAAAUGUGGUAUCUGAGUGCCUUGUAGCAUUCAGAAUUUAGCAUGACAAGUUGCUCGUAGGCUAUUCCAUCAAGACAUUCCCACUACAGCUCAGCUGCAAACAUCUAGAGCAAGCUCCCGUAGGGUUGUAUUUUAAGCUAGCUGUGAGCUAAUUAUAUGGCAAUUUGUAUCUUAGAAUCCAUGUAGAACAAUAUUUGGAGCAUUAGGUUGAGAGAUUAUGACUGCUAAAAUAAUUUCCUGAUGCUGUCAUGCAUCGGGUUUUGACAGUUGCACAACAGUAAUAAAGCCUCCAUUUAUUAGGAGCUUAAAACAUAUCAGGACUUUACAUACAUGAUACCUUAUCCCUAAAACAAAUCUGCCAUUCAGAUAUAUACACACCAUCUAUACAUGUUGCAUAUGUGGGGGCUGAGACAACAUAGGUUACUAGGGAGGAAUUUGAGUGUUGGUCUGACAGUAAAGCUUGGGUUCUUUCUACUUUAGCAUGAGUACAAACAUUUCGUUUUAAGUUUGUGUACAUGAAAAAUAGAUGUAAAAUUGUCUCAGAAGACUUUUGAGAUUUUAAUGUUGAAUAACUGUUUAGAAACUUGGGGUCUUUAGACUCUCAAAUGGUAGAACAUUCAUGUUCUAUUUCUUAAAAUUGAUAUAGCUUUAUUGGCAAUAGUACUGAAUUUGGAGUAGGGGCAUUUGUGUGUAUAUAUGUAUAAAAUAAAGAACUUAAUAUUUCAUUGUGGAAGUUACAGUGAGAAGCAUCCUUUGGUAUUUUUUGUAAUUUUGGCACUCAUUAGAAAUAAGCCAUUUAUUCUGUCACGUUGAAACACUGACUAUAGUGAAUUUGUCACUAAAUUUUAAUAUGUUCGUUCGGCAGUAGAUUUUGAUUGAUUGUACUGGCUGGAGCCUAUUCUUGAUGCUCUUUAGCUUUACAGUUUAUAUUUUCAGCAGACAUUGAUGCCCUGUGCCCCCUCCAUUGCAGAGUUUCAAUUGCUUGCUGAAGAGUUAGUGUUGAAUUUGGUGGCCACUCUCUGUUCACUAAAACCUGUGUCUGAUUAGGGUCAGUUUUGGAAGUGCCCACCUAAGACUAUUCCAUUACAGUAGCCUUUUCUUUUUUGCAGCUCUUCAGUACAAGAGCCUCAUGUCCCACUCCACCCCAUCCAUCUUUUGUGCCUAUUCUUCAGUGAAAAUACUCUUAUUUAACCCGAAUCUUUUCUGAAAGUGCUUCUUCUCACUUCUCAUCCCAGGAGAGAGACUCGACUUUCUCUCUCCUAUUUUUCUUGCCUUCAAAUUGAAACCACCUCCUUCCAUUCAUCUGGAACCACAGGUUCUGGGCCCUUGCAUGUGCUGGUGUCUCUACUUGGAGAACCUUUCCUUGACGUGUUCACAGGUGAACUCUAACUCAUUCCUUGUGACUUAGUUUGAGUAUUACCUUCCCCAUGAAACUUUCCCUCAGCAAGUGAGUAAUAAUGAUUUUUAAAGCAAUAAUAUGUGUCAGACAAAGUACUAGAAACUUUACAAGUGUUAUAUAGUUAGUCCUCACAACAAUUACAUAAGAUAGUUGCUGCUGGCCGGGUGCGUUGGCUCACUUCUGUAAUCCCAGCACUUUGGGAGGCCGAGGCAGGCAGAUUAUGAGGUCAGGAGAUCGAAACCAUCCUGGCUAACAUGGUGAAAUCCCCAUCUCUACUAAAAAUACAAAAAAAUUAGCUGGGCGUGGUGGUGGGCGCCUGUAGUCCCAGCUACUCGGGAGGCUGAGGCAGGAGAAUGGCGUGAACCCGGGAGGUGGAGCUUGCAGUGAGCCGAGAUCACGCCACUGCACUCCAGCCUGGGUGACAGAUCGAGACUCUGUCUCAAAAAAAUAAAUAAAUAAAUAAAUAAAAAAUAAAAAUAAAAAAGAUAGUUACUGCUGUUAUCUUUGCUUUACAUACAGGGGAACUGAGCUAAUAAGGGAUAGGAGUAGAAUUCAAACCCUGGUAUCUCUCAUUCUAAAAAUUGUAUGUGUCCCACUGGAUCAUGUUACUUCCUGGGCCACUCCAUCUUUUGUAUCACUUUUAUACUUUGUUCAUAUUUAUUAUCAUUAUCGUAAUCAUUAUGAGUGAAACCUAUGCCUUCAUAAUCUCUUUAUCCAUAAUUCAGUCCUUAGUAUAUCACAGGUAUUAAAGUGUGUGCUGGAUAUAUACAUAAACUAUUAGAUGGCUGGAUUCUCAUUUGGCCUGUUCUCUUGGACCUCUGAUGCUCUUUGCUGGACUCCUAACUGCCCUCUAGAUGCUCUUACUGGUCAGACUUAUAGAAAACUUGCCAUUAAGUGCCUUUUCUUAUUGGGUAGUUCUGGUGCCACAUGCACUCUUCUCUUCUUUCCUGUUUUGCUGAAUUUAACAGCCAUGGCACAUUUAUUCCUCAGCUGUGACAUUCUAAAUGCUUUUGUUCUGGCUACGAGUCUGGGAUUUGUGUGCUGUGGAUAACUGGCUCAUCACUGGGAUCAAAGGAAACAGGCUCUCCCAGAAAACAAGCAUUCUUACUUGAAAUUACGUGGCUGGGGAGCCUGGAAAGUUAUCUUAUGUCUCACAUGAAUCUUUUUGGUCUUAGCUAUGAUUUACACGCUUUAUUAUGAAAGAAAAACAAACCAGUUAUUGUUAGUUACUCUGUCUGCAAAAAUAUUGAUAUUUUGUUGAAUAUGAAGAUAUUAAUAAUAAUGUUUAUUAUGACCAAUGCCUAUAGAUGUUGGGGAGUAGGUAAGGCCAGGAGAAGCCCUUGGGUUUGACAAUAUGGUCCAUCACCAAAAUAAAUACUUAUGUGUUUAUAUCCUUCUAGACUCCUGAAAACCAAAAAUGUUGUCUAGAACAUAAGAUGGGGGUGCAGUUAUAGCAUCUUGUCUGAUAGGAAGCCUUUCAGAAUCAGGUGGAAAUUUAGCCUGGCUGGAGUCAGGCUAGGUGUAGGGGUUUUGAAGUUUUGCUCUGAAAGGAAAGCUACAAGAUGGAGUGAGGACUGCAUUAUGGUGGAGGUGCAGUUUUUGGCCUUGGAGACUCCACAGAUACAUUCAGACUUCUUUUACAUGUCAGGUCAUUGUCUGCCUUAUGCUGGGUACUUGCCUUGUUUAUUGUAUUUGUAAGCUCCAAAACACUGUUUCCAUCAAUCAGUUAAUGACUUUCAGUCAAUAAUCCUUACUUAAUGGACGUCUUUUGCUGGACAUAAAUGGCAAUGUAAAUAGGACAUGGUUCCUGCCCUGGAGGGGCUCACAGUUCAGAGUAGUUUUUGUUGUUGUUUCUGUUUUAUUAAAUUAAUAUUAUUUCUGCUAAAACUUGAAGACAGGGAUUUUGGAAUCUGUUGUUGGUGUUUUGUUGUAGACUGUUUGGAGUUGUCAAGUUUGCAGAGGUCUGGCUAUAAGGGGAAAGUUGCCUGGACCCUUCGAUUGUGCUUUCAACCCUUGAAAGUGAUCUUGAGGAUCAGAGUGCCUUUCCUCAUGUGGAAUGAAACAUCCAAGUCAGAAUGUUACAUCACACAUUUCCUCAGCUAACUACCUAGUUUCCUGGAAAGUUGCUGGCUUUGGACAGCUCCUCUCUCUCGGUACUCUUGAGAAUGUUUGACGUAGAGGACAGGCACUCUGACUAUGGAAUUUUACAUUAAUAUAUUUAUUAGUGAAAAAGUUUUAAUUGGUGCUUGAUAGUCAAAGCUAGCAGACUUCCCAGAUUUACUCUCAAAUUCCUGAUCUUAUUGAUCUUUUGCUUAUUGGAUUAAGAUUCCUGAGUAUGAGGAGACUAUUUUCUUUUCAGCUUCCUGGAUGGAGCACAGCAGAGCCUUCCUGUUUGGAUCCUUAGAGUGGUUUUACUUCUUCAAGAAUCUAUUGAAUUUUUUGUCUGCCUUAGCUACAUGUGGGCCCCCUUGCUCGCUCUUAGACCUAUUCUCUGAUUUCAUGAAGGGGAAGGCGGGAUUAUUUCCUUUUUCUUACAAUAUUUUUUCUUCUAUUUUUUAUCUUUUUCUUUUCUAGGCAGGGCCACUACUUCUCAGCACAUCCGGCCUUCUGGCUCAUCUCCUCCCUGCAUCUCACUACGCCCCUCCCCACUCCAGGGUAAAUUCCAAUAAUGCUGCUCUGUUCCAGAUGGAGUUCAUGUUGACUGAGGUGAAUUUUAGGGCUGUAACUGGUUUGGUCUGAUCUGGAUCCCCAUUAUAAUAUUGAAAUCUCUACAGUGGAGGCCUGAAGUUAAAUCAUUUUGGAAAGUGAUACAGGAGAGGACUCUGCUAUGAAACUUCCUGAGUGAAAUGAUAAGUGGCAUGAAGAAAAACAAAGCAAGCUCUCACGUGUGAAUAUGUGUCUAGUGCAUCCUUAACCUGAGGACUUCACCAGUUCGAAAUUACAGUUUUCACCAUCAACUACCUUAUCCUUUUUGGCCUGGUUUUCUUCCUCAAACAGUGGAAACAUUUUUAAAGUUGCUUUUGUUGCAGAGUUAAACAAAUGGCUGAUAGUGGCUUAGAUAAAAAAUCCACAAAAUGCCCCGACUGUUCAUCUGCUUCUCAGAAAGAUGUACUUUGUGUAUGUUCCAGCAAAACAAGGGUUCCUCCAGUUUUGGUGGUGGAAAUGUCACAGACAUCAAGCAUUGGUAGUGCAGAAUCUUUAAUUUCACUGGAGAGAAAAAAAGAAAAAAAUAUCAACAGAGAUAUAACCUCCAGGAAAGAUUUGCCCUCAAGAACCUCAAAUGUAGAGAGAAAAGCAUCUCAGCAACAAUGGGGUCGGGGCAACUUUACAGAAGGAAAAGUUCCUCACAUAAGGAUUGAGAAUGGAGCUGCUAUUGAGGAAAUCUAUACCUUUGGAAGAAUAUUGGGAAAAGGGAGCUUUGGAAUAGUCAUUGAAGCGACAGACAAGGAAACAGAAACGAAGUGGGCAAUUAAAAAAGUGAACAAAGAAAAGGCUGGAAGCUCUGCUGUGAAGUUACUUGAACGAGAGGUGAACAUUCUGAAAAGUGUAAAACAUGAACACAUCAUACAUCUGGAACAAGUAUUUGAAACGCCAAAGAAAAUGUACCUUGUGAUGGAGCUUUGUGAGGAUGGAGAACUCAAAGAAAUUCUGGAUAGGAAAGGGCAUUUCUCAGAGAAUGAGACAAGGUGGAUCAUUCAAAGUCUCGCAUCAGCUAUAGCAUAUCUUCACAAUAAUGAUAUUGUACAUAGAGAUCUGAAACUGGAAAAUAUAAUGGUUAAAAGCAGUCUUAUUGAUGAUAACAAUGAAAUAAACUUAAACAUAAAGGUGACUGAUUUUGGCUUAGCGGUGAAGAAGCAAAGUAGGAGUGAAGCCAUGCUGCAGGCCACAUGUGGGACUCCUAUCUAUAUGGCCCCUGAAGUUAUCAGUGCCCACGACUAUAGCCAGCAGUGUGACAUUUGGAGCAUAGGCGUCGUAAUGUACAUGUUAUUACGUGGAGAACCACCCUUUUUGGCAAGCUCAGAAGAGAAGCUUUUUGAGUUAAUAAGAAAAGGAGAACUACAUUUUGAAAAUGCAGUCUGGAAUUCCAUAAGUGACUGUGCUAAAAGUGUUUUGAAACAACUUAUGAAAGUAGAUCCUGCUCACAGAAUCACAGCUAAGGAACUACUAGAUAACCAGUGGUUAACAGGCAAUAAACUUUCUUCGGUGAGACCAACCAAUGUAUUAGAGAUGAUGAAGGAAUGGAAAAAUAACCCAGAAAGUGUUGAGGAAAACACAACAGAAGAGAAGAAUAAGCCGUCCACUGAAGAAAAGUUGAAAAGUUACCAACCCUGGGGAAAUGUCCCUGAUGCCAAUUACACUUCAGAUGAAGAGGAGGAAAAACAGGACAAUGCUGGCCUACGCAGUCUCAGAGCAUGAAAGUUUGAGGCGUCUAUGUUAUGAGAGAGUGGACAUGAAGGUGCUUUGAAUAGAUCCAUCUUCACAGGGAGGACACUGGCUGUCAGGAGAGACCAGACUUGCCUCAAGAAGGGUUAAUGCCCAAAGCAGGACCUUUUGGAGGUCGUCAGCCUUCACUAGUACCAG